AGAAUUCUUAGUUGUUUUCUUUAGAAGAACAUUUCUAGGGAAUAAUACAAGAAGAUUUAGGAAUCAUUGAAGUUAUAAAUCUUUGGAAUGAGCAAACUCAGAAUGGUGCUACUUGAAGACUCUGGAUCUGCUGACUUCAGAAGACAUUUUGUCAACUUGAGUCCCUUCACCAUUACUGUGGUCUUACUUCUCAGUGCCUGUUUUGUCACCAGUUCUCUUGGAGGAACAGACAAGGAGCUGAGGCUAGUGGAUGGUGAAAACAAGUGUAGCGGGAGAGUGGAAGUGAAAGUCCAGGAGGAGUGGGGAACGGUGUGUAAUAAUGGCUGGAGCAUGGAAGCGGUCUCUGUGAUUUGUAACCAGCUGGGAUGUCCAACUGCUAUCAAAGCCCCUGGAUGGGCUAAUUCCAGUGCAGGUUCUGGACGCAUUUGGAUGGAUCAUGUUUCUUGUCGUGGGAAUGAGUCAGCUCUUUGGGAUUGCAAACAUGAUGGAUGGGGAAAGCAUAGUAACUGUACUCACCAACAAGAUGCUGGAGUGACCUGCUCAGAUGGAUCCAAUUUGGAAAUGAGGCUGACGCGUGGAGGGAAUAUGUGUUCUGGAAGAAUAGAGAUCAAAUUCCAAGGACGGUGGGGAACAGUGUGUGAUGAUAACUUCAACAUAGAUCAUGCAUCUGUCAUUUGUAGACAACUUGAAUGUGGAAGUGCUGUCAGUUUCUCUGGUUCAUCUAAUUUUGGAGAAGGCUCUGGACCAAUCUGGUUUGAUGAUCUUAUAUGCAACGGAAAUGAGUCAGCUCUCUGGAACUGCAAACAUCAAGGAUGGGGAAAGCAUAACUGUGAUCAUGCUGAGGAUGCUGGAGUGAUUUGCUCAAAGGGAGCAGAUCUGAGCCUGAGACUGGUAGAUGGAGUCACUGAAUGUUCAGGAAGAUUAGAAGUGAGAUUCCAAGGAGAAUGGGGGACAAUAUGUGAUGACGGCUGGGACAGUUACGAUGCUGCUGUGGCAUGCAAGCAACUGGGAUGUCCAACUGCCGUCACAGCCAUUGGUCGAGUUAACGCCAGUAAGGGAUUUGGACACAUCUGGCUUGACAGCGUUUCUUGCCAGGGACAUGAACCUGCUAUCUGGCAAUGUAAACACCAUGAAUGGGGAAAGCAUUAUUGCAAUCACAAUGAAGAUGCUGGCGUGACAUGUUCUGAUGGAUCAGAUCUGGAGCUAAGACUUAGAGGUGGAGGCAGCCGCUGUGCUGGGACAGUUGAGGUGGAGAUUCAGAGACUGUUAGGGAAGGUGUGUGACAGAGGCUGGGGACUGAAAGAAGCUGAUGUGGUUUGCAGGCAGCUGGGAUGUGGAUCUGCACUCAAAACAUCUUAUCAAGUGUACUCCAAAAUCCAGGCAACAAACACAUGGCUGUUUCUAAGUAGCUGUAACGGAAAUGAAACUUCUCUUUGGGACUGCAAGAACUGGCAAUGGGGUGGACUUACCUGUGAUCACUAUGAAGAAGCCAAAAUUACCUGCUCAGCCCACAGGGAACCCAGACUGGUUGGAGGGGACAUUCCCUGUUCUGGACGUGUUGAAGUGAAGCAUGGUGACACGUGGGGCUCCAUCUGUGAUUCGGACUUCUCUCUGGAAGCUGCCAGCGUUCUAUGCAGGGAAUUACAGUGUGGCACAGUUGUCUCUAUCCUGGGGGGAGCUCACUUUGGAGAGGGAAAUGGACAGAUCUGGGCUGAAGAAUUCCAGUGUGAGGGACAUGAGUCCCAUCUUUCACUCUGCCCAGUAGCACCCCGCCCAGAAGGAACUUGUAGCCACAGCAGGGAUGUUGGAGUAGUCUGCUCAAGAUACACAGAAAUUCGCUUGGUGAAUGGCAAGACCCCGUGUGAGGGCAGAGUGGAGCUCAAAACGCUUGGUGCCUGGGGAUCCCUCUGUAACUCUCACUGGGACAUAGAAGAUGCCCAUGUUCUUUGCCAGCAGCUUAAAUGUGGAGUUGCCCUUUCUACCCCAGGAGGAGCACGUUUUGGAAAAGGAAAUGGUCAGAUCUGGAGGCAUAUGUUUCACUGCACUGGGACUGAGCAGCACAUGGGAGAUUGUCCUGUAACUGCUCUAGGUGCUUCAUUAUGUCCUUCAGAGCAAGUGGCCUCUGUAAUCUGCUCAGGAAACCAGUCCCAAACACUGUCCUCGUGCAAUUCAUCGUCUUUGGGCCCAACAAGGCCUACCAUUCCAGAAGAAAGUGCUGUGGCCUGCAUAGAGAGUGGUCAACUUCGCCUGGUAAAUGGAGGAGGUCGCUGUGCUGGGAGAGUAGAGAUCUAUCAUGAGGGCUCCUGGGGCACCAUCUGUGAUGACAGCUGGGACCUGAGUGAUGCCCACGUGGUUUGCAGACAGCUGGGCUGUGGAGAGGCCAUUAAUGCCACUGGUUCUGCUCAUUUUGGGGAAGGAACAGGGCCCAUCUGGCUGGAUGAGAUGAAAUGCAAUGGAAAAGAAUCCCGCAUUUGGCAGUGCCAUUCACACGGCUGGGGGCAGCAAAAUUGCAGGCACAAGGAGGAUGCGGGAGUUAUCUGCUCAGAAUUCAUGUCUCUGAGACUGACCAGUGAAGCCAGCAGAGAGGCCUGUGCAGGGCGUCUGGAAGUUUUUUACAAUGGAGCUUGGGGCACUGUUGGCAAGAGUAGCAUGUCUGAAACCACUGUGGGUGUGGUGUGCAGGCAGCUGGGCUGUGCAGACAAAGGGAAAAUCAACCCUGCAUCUUUAGACAAGGCCAUGUCCAUUCCCAUGUGGGUGGACAAUGUUCAGUGUCCAAAAGGACCUGACACGCUGUGGCAGUGCCCAUCAUCUCCAUGGGAGAAGAGACUGGCCAGCCCCUCGGAGGAGACCUGGAUCACAUGUGACAACAAGAUAAGACUUCAGGAAGGACCCACUUCCUGUUCUGGACGUGUGGAGAUCUGGCAUGGAGGUUCCUGGGGGACAGUGUGUGAUGACUCUUGGGACUUGGACGAUGCUCAGGUGGUGUGUCAACAACUUGGCUGUGGUCCAGCUUUGAAAGCAUUCAAAGAAGCAGAGUUUGGUCAGGGGACUGGACCGAUAUGGCUCAAUGAAGUGAAGUGCAAAGGGAAUGAGUCUUCCUUGUGGGAUUGUCCUGCCAGACGCUGGGGCCAUAGUGAGUGUGGGCACAAGGAAGACGCUGCAGUGAAUUGCACAGAUAUUUCAGUGCAGAAAACCCCACAAAAAGCCACAACAGGUCGCUCAUCCCGUCAGUCAUCCUUUAUUGCAGUCGGGAUCCUUGGGGUUGUUCUGUUGGCCAUUUUCGUCGCAUUAUUCUUCUUGACUAAAAAGCGAAGACAGAGACAGCGGCUUGCAGUUUCCUCAAGAGGAGAGAACUUAGUCCACCAAAUUCAAUACCGGGAGAUGAAUUCUUGCCUGAAUGCAGAUGAUCUGGACCUAAUGAAUUCCUCAGGUCUGUGGGUUCUUGGAGGGUCUAUUGCCCAGGGGUUCAGAUCAGUGGCUGCAGUUGAGGCACAGACAUUCUACUUUGAUAAACAGUUAAAAAAGUCUAAAAAUGUAAUAGGAAGCUUAGAUGCAUAUAAUGGACAAGAAUGACUGAAAAUUAUUCUUGGAGAAUAUCAAAAUUGCAAUCAUAGGGAGGCCUUUAGCUUAAGAGGCCUGUGAUUAUUCCUGAUAGAGGUAUGGAAAGAACCAUGCAGAGGAAUAUUAUGACUUGGACCUCAUUUUAUUAAAACAGAAAUUAAUCUUACAAAAGAUUGUCAUAAGUGACAGUUUAACUUUUUUCUUUAAAUUUUGUUGUGUAUAUUUAAGGUAUACAACAUGAUUUUAUGGGAUGUAUAUAGAUAGUAAAAAGCUUACUAAAGCAAAGCAAAUGAACACACCCAUCAUCUGACAUAGUUACCCUUUUUUGUGUUGUUCUUGUGGCAAGAGCAGCUAAAACCUACUCACUUAGCAUGAAUCCUACAUACAGCACAAUGUUAUUACCUAUAAUCCUCAUGUUGUACAUUAGACCUCUAGACUGGUUCAUUCUACGUAUCUGCUACUUUGUAUCCUCUGACCUACAUACGUCUUUCACAGUUUCUUCCAUUCCCAUUUCCUGUCAUUUUUUUUCUCUAGCUUGAUAUUUAUUAUAUUUUUCCCUAAAAGUCUAAAACCUUAAACUUUCAAUAUCUUUAUUGCAUGAGAAGCCAUACAAAUCCACAGAACUAGCCUUAUUUCUCAUCACAUCAUGCUGUUUUAUCCUUGAACUUCUAUUUAGCACCAGUGCACUAAUUCUGCAUCUGGGCAGGAUGACUUUACUGGGUUGGAAGAAAUAUCCCAAAACCCAUUGUCUUUACUCCAUGAAGGGUCCCUGACCUUCUGAGAGGGGCCUGCCUCACUUCUUCCAUCCAAAGAAUUAUGCAUCUGCUACUGUGUCAGGGAACAUAUUUAAGGAACAUGUACUGUUACUGUGUCAGGAAACAUAUUUAAGAAAUAGGAAAGACUUUCUCUGCCCCUUAAAUCACACAUGCUUUUCUUCCUAGUUAUGGGUGGUGUUUUUAGUUG